AGACAGCCUCCCACUGUCGCCCAAGCUAGAGUGCAAUGGCGUGAUCUUAGCUCGCGGCAACCUCUGCCUCUCAGGUUCAAGCGAUUCUUAUGCCUCAGUCCCCUGAGUAGCUGGGAUUACAGGCAUGUGCCACUAUACCUGACUAAUUUUUGUAUUUUAAGUAGAGACAGGGUUUCACCAUGUUGGUCAGGCUGGUCUCAAAUUCCCAACCUCAGGUGAUCCACCCACCUCGGCCUCCCAACGUGCUGGGAUUACAGGCGUGAGCCACUGCACCCAGACAGGAUUAUUCUUACUUAUUUAUUUAUAGGUCUCAAAGCAUUUUUAAAAGGUCACAAUCAAUCUACCGUUUUAUGUAAAGCCUUUAAAAGAGACAGUAAGCUGAAUGAUCCAUUUAGUUAUUUUUUGGUGAGGAAGGGGUGGUAGGAAGAAGAGAAUGUCAUCCAUGUUUCUUAAUUUUCUUUUUUUGUGUGUAUUUUUCUUUUUUUCUAUUAAAAAAUGGAUGGCACAAUUUUUUUUCUAUAAAAAACCUGUACUCUUAUUUAUAUAUCAUUUUAGUUCAGCAGCCACCAUUAUAUUUAACAUAGUACCUAUUUCUAUUCUAUAUUAUGAUUUUUUUGUGUGUGUGUGUGAGAUGAAGUCUCACUCUAUUGCCCAGGCUGGAGUGCAGUGGUGUGAUCUUGGCUCACUACAAUCUCUGCCUCCCAGGUUCAAGCGAUUCUCCCGCCUCAGCCUUCCAAGUAGCUGAGAUUACAGGCACUUGCCACCAGACCCGGCUAAUUUUUUUGUAUUUUUAGUAGAGAUUGGGUUUCACCAUGUUGGCCAGGAUGGUUUUGAACUCCUGACCUCAAAUGAUCCGCCCCCCUCAACCUCCCAAAGUGCUAAGGUUACCAAUGUGAGCCACCAUGCCUGGCUCAUAUUAUAUUAUCCAUAAUUGAUAAUGAUUUCGUUUCUUAAAUAGCAUUUCCAAUUUAUUUUGCUAUUGAUGACAUGCUAUUCUUUGUAGCUGAUUCAUCACUUUUUAAAAUCUGUCUCACAGCAGCUCAUGUAGUAUUGGACGUUUAAAGAUACUUUGAAGAUAAAUGUUUUGGGUGUUAAAGAUGUUUUAAAUGACAUUUUUUUUUUUUGAGACGGAGUCUCGCUCUGUCGCCCAGGCUGGAGUGAAGUGGCACGAUCUCUGCUCACUGCAAGCUCCGCCUCCCGGGUUCACGCCAUUCUCCUGCCUCAGCCUCCCGAGUAGCUGGGACAACAGGCGCCCGCCACCGCGCCAGGCAAUUUUUUGUAUUUUUAGUAGAGACGGUGUUUCACUGUGUCAGCCAGGAUGGUCUCAAUCCCCUGACCUCGUGAUCCGCCCAUCUUGGCCUCCCAAAGUGUUGGGAUUACAGGCGUGAGCCACCACGCCCAGCCAAAUGACAUUUAAAUGAUAACUAUAUGUGACUUAAUGACACUUUCUUUAUGCCGCUUUCACCCAUUCUUACUAUACACAGACUCUAGGGAAAACUGAGGUGCUGCUUUGUUUUCAUCUCCCAAAUGGGGCUUUAUUCAUUUAGUCAUAAACCUACUUCCCUCAGUAUUAGAGAAGUCUUUCAUUAAGUACUGGCCAAAUAAGUUUAUUCUGUCUGAUGGCUUAAAUAGGUUAAAAGAAAUAUACCUGCUAUAUUGUGGAACAUUAGGUAACUUAAAGUAGGUUUUUGAAUCCUAAAAUCAUAUAACACAAAAUACAAUAAAGGGACAUCUCUUCCUCCUUGGUCCUGGAGUUGUCUUACCACUUAUUGAUUUUUUUUAUUGUAUUUUUAUUUUAUGAGACAGAGUCUCGCUGUCGCCAGGCUGGGGUGCAGUGGCGCGAUCUUGGCUCACUGCAACCUCGGCCUCCUGGGUUCAAGUGAUUCUCCUGCCUCAGCUUCCCGAGUAGCUGAGACUUACAGGCGCACAUCACCACACCCAGCUAAUUUUUGUAUUUUUAGUAGAGAAGGGGUUUCACCAUGUUGGCAAGGAUGGUGUCGAUCUCUUGACCUCGUGAUCCGCCUGCCUCGGCCUCCCAAAGUGUUGGGAUUACAGGCGUGAGCCACCGUGCCUGGCCCAUUUUAUUUUUAAAGCAUGAAGUAGAACAUUUUGAAAACCUGUGCUCUGUAAUAUGAAUAUUUACUGCUUUUCAUAGUCUCAUUUAAAAUACAAAGCCUAAAUAGCCGGGCGUGGUGGCACACACCUGUAAUCCCAACUAUUCCGGAGGCUGAGGUGGGAGAAUCGCUUGAACCCAGGAGGUGGAGGUUGCAGUGAGCUGAGAUUGCACCACUGCACUCUAGCCUGGGUGACAGAGUGAGACGCUGUCUCAAAAACAAAAAACAAAACAAACAAAAAAACCCCAAAGCCUUAAAUUGCAAUUUUGUUAGAAAAGUAACAUUUGAAACCUUGUAUCAAAUGUAUUUAUUAUAAAAAUAAUACACGCUUUUAAGCACUUUUUAAAGUAUAGAAAUAAAGUAAAAAUGAAAGUCCUCUAUUUUCUCAUUUUACUCCAUAGCUAAUAUAAUUCAGACUUUCAGGAAUUUAGUUUUUAAAUUUAAAAGUUCUUGGCCAAUCAAAAAAUCUUUUUCAGGCUGGUCAUGGUGGCUCAUGCCUGUAAUCUCAGCCCUUUGGGAGACUGUGGCAGGAGGAUCACUUGAGCUCAGGAAUUCAAGAGCAGCCUGGGUAACAUAGUGAGAUCUUGUCUCUACAAGAAAAAAAAAAAGGCUAGGUAUGGUGGCACAUGCCUGUGGUCCUGCUACUUGGGAGGCUAAUACAGGAGGAUUGCUCGACCUGGGGAGGUUGAGGCUGCAGUGAGCCCUAUUCCUGCCACUGCACUCCAACCUGAGAGACAGAGCGAGACCCAGUCUCCAAAUUUUUUUUUUAAAGUUUCACCUCUUAAAAGCUAACUUUAAAAUAGUAAGUAUGCCUCCUUUAUUAAUGCUGUCACUGUAGCCUCAUUUGUUUCCUACAUCACAGGCUAAUGAAUAUAUGACUCUAACUUAAGAUUCUCUUGAAAACUAAGCCCAAAAUAGGAAGGAAAGAAAGAAGGUGGGAGGAAGCCAGUGGCAAUAUAUUUUUCAUUAUUGUGUGCCUUUUAAGUGUAGAAUUCAGUGGUUUUCAGUGUAUUUAUGGAGUUGGGUGUCUUAGGCAUAAUUGAGACAUUCUGAUUUCUUAGGUCUUGAAAUUUCAAUGUUUAUUUUUUAAAAGUUUUUAUUAUGGGGAAUUUCAGAUAUACCCUAAAGUAGAAGAGUAUAAUGAACCCCAGUGUCCAUUCCUCAUCUUCCCCUCACAGCCAGUCUUCUUCCAUCUUUUCCCUCAUUUACUCCACCAGGGUUAUUUUGAAGCAAAUUCCAGAUGUUAUAUUAUUCUGUAAAUAUUUCAGUCUGUAUCUAUAUAAGAUGAUUUUUUAAAAAUGACCACAGUAAUGUUCACAUUAAAAAAAUUUAAUAAUUACUUAAUAUUAAAUAACCAGUGUUCAAAUUUCUAAUAAAUGUAAAAAGCUUAGUUUUGUUUUAUAACUUAUAGAGGAUAAUUUUUAUUAACUUGUUAGAGAAAAGUUGGAUGUCAUACUAAAUAUUUAUACAAUGUAUUUUAAUAUCUACUUCAAAUGAAUUUAUGUCACUGAAGUAAAAUCCCACGGAUUCCUAUAUAUAUAUACACACAUAUAUAUACGUAUAUAUAUGUGUAUAUAUAUAUACACAUAUAUACGUAUAUGUGUGUAUAUAUAUACACAUAUACGUAUAUAUGUGUAUAUAUAUAUACACAUAUAUAUACGUAUAUGUGUAUAUAUAUACACAUGUAUAUACACAUAUACGUAUAUAUAUGUGUAUAUAUACGUAUAUAUGUAUUUUUUUUUUUUUUUGAGUCAGAGUUUUGCUCUUGUCACCCAGGCUGGAGUGCAGUGGCGUGAUCUUGGCUCACUACAACCUCUUCUUCCCGGAUUCAAGCGAUUCUCCUGCCUCAGCCUCCUGAGUAGCUGGGAUUACAGGCAUGCGCCACUAUGCCCGGCUAAUUUUUUUGUAUUUUUAGUAGAGUUGGAGUUUCACCAUGUUGGCCAGGCUGAUCUCAAGCUCCUGACCUGAGAUGAUCCACCUGCCUCAGCCUCCCAAAGUGCUGGGAUUACAGGCAUGGGCCACCCCCGCCGGCCCCAAAAUAUAUUUAACUUCCUGUCUUCCUGGACGAAAAAGUUAUUCUCUUACCUUUCCAUGAAUAUACACUUGGUUUGAGAUUUCCUCGUCUUACACUUCUUAUUUACAGGACUUAGGGAGCCUGAACAUUCUGUACUGAGGAAACAGAACAGAGGGCUGGAUAUUGCAGAAGUCCAUCUUGCCUUCAUAAUGGUGCUCUUAUGGUAUAAGUGAUGAAUUCAUCUGGGGGUGGAGUGAGGGAGUGGGCAGGGGAGAUUAUCAUGGAUUUACUACCACUUAUAGUGCCAAUAUGUUUAAAAAAAGGAAAGACUUUGGGGCCUCAGCCAAUUUUUAACUUUGGAUGAAGUAACUUGCUUUUGCGAGCGCCAUUAGAUAAGGGAAAGGGACUUCUGAAGGCUAAAUAACCCAUUAACUGUAUCUCCCUAAGAAGAUACAGUUAGAGUAACAACAGCAUAGGAAUAACCAUAGUCAUUUAGAAUUGUGUACAGGUCAAAUCCCGUUACAACAAUUUCAGAAGAGUAUCUAACUUAUUUGUCUUAAAGCUUAUACUGCAAAGUAUUAAUAUGUAAUAUAUCAGAUUAUAGAACUUUUUUGUUCUUAAGUUUCUUUGGAGAAAAAAACACAAGGACUUUUGAAGGGGCAUUUCUAAUUAACCCCACAGCCAGCUUCCUUGUUACCAAGACCCUGGAUGGGAAUUUGCUAUCACUGGUUGGCUGCGUGGCACCAGGCAGCUCGUUGGGCUCACUUGCCUCGUGCUAUACCACUCCGGAGUGUUCAUUUAUUCAUGCAGCCUAAAAAGUGUAGUGGGCAUCGAGAUUUGCUUGGUGCUCUGGGAGAAGACUAACAUCAAUAAAAGACGCAGUCCCUAUUCAUUAGGAAUUUACAGACUGCUUGGAAGAGGCGACCCGCAAAGCAGAGUCUAAGGAACGAUGCGGCCACGAGAGUGUUUGGAAUUAGGGUGAAGGGAAGCUUUCCAGCGCCUACCACAUCGCACAUCAAACCAUCUGCAAAGAUCUGAAAGCAUUUUUGUAGUAUUUUGAUUUUUAUAGCUUUCAUUGUAACGGGAUUUAACCUGUAACAUCUUUUCAUCAGAGAACUGCAGAUUACACAAAUGAAAAUAUCAUAAAUCCCCAUUUGUACUUUCUGUACUUUGUACCAAAUGUACUUAACUGUAUGCUAAAUAUAGUAUUGAAUAUGUAUCAGUGCAAACGUUAAGAGCCUUUUGCAAAUAGAUUUAUGAACAUGGAUACUUAUUUUGUUUACUUUUAUAUUACAUGUACUGUUUAUACAAAACAUGCAUUAAAACGUCUGUAAUGUUAUUUCAGUGUGUGAUGGAUGAGUGGUUGCUUUAAAUCACUAGGUUUUUGAUUGGUGCUAGAGUAGCUGGUGUUGCUUAACGUGGCAUUUUUUUUCCUGUCCACACUUUCCACCCUUGGUACAGGUAUUUUUGAUAAAGCUGUGGAAUGGAAAGGUAUGUUUUUCAUGGGGUGUUCAAGAAUCUGUUACCUUAAAUUUUUUUAAAGAGGUUUCCUUUCUGGGAUUCCUUUUGUGUCUGGCUUAAGCAGACUUAGUUUAAUUUAACAAGUAACAUUUUUAGAGGCAGUAUUUGAGUAUAAAAGUUUGACGUGACACAAGUUUCUGACUUUACUUUUCCCCAUUCCCUUAUUAAAGAUAGUACGAAGGAUUUUAAAGCAUUUGGGGUGGGGGGUUGCUCUUAAAAUAUAUGAUCUGUACCAUGAGAAAGAAUGUAGCCCAAGGGUUGUUUAUGGUAGUUAAUGAUCUAGUGUGUUGUUAUUGCUAGAAUCCUGGUUAUCAUAAAUUUGCAAUUUCAUUGAGGAAAGUGAUAUAAGUAUUUCUUAAUAUAUUAAUAUAUGAAAUAAUUUUAGAGACUUUAUUAAAUACACACAGUCCUCUUUAUGGUAGAGGAACAGUUCAGCUUGAGCUGGUGACCGGCUGAACUAGAGGGGUUACUCUGGGAAAGUGGCGAGUCGGCAGGGCAUGUCUGCACAGAUUUUGUGCCAGGUUUCCUGCCUGCACAGCGCUUUCUUCUCUGUCCAAGUUCUGUGCUGACCACAGCUGUCCACAGGCAUGUUUACACUCCCUGUUCUUGCAGGUUGACUUGAGAGAACCACGUAGCUAAAUUGGUGAGAGACUCAGCCUGACCGCUUGUCUUUAGAAGGCCUGAUUGGAAGAGUGCACUCUAUUGACUUUCCUCUAACAAUGAAAUUGUGAAAGAGGUCCUGUAAUAAAGAGGGAUCCGAACAAGCUCAGAAAGAAAAUGAAUUUCAAGGGGCUGAGGCCAUGGUUCUGGAGAGCGUUAUGUUUGCCAUUCUCGCAGAGAGGUCACUUGGGCCAAAACUCUAUGGCAUCUUUCCCCAAGGCCGACUGGAGCAGUUCAUCCCGAGCCGGCGAUUAGAUACUGAAGAAUUAAGUUUGCCAGAUAUUUCUGCAGAAAUCGCCGAGAAAAUGGCUACAUUUCAUGGUAUGAAAAUGCCAUUCAAUAAGGAACCAAAAUGGCUUUUUGGCACAAUGGAAAAGUAUCUAAAGGAAGUGCUGAGAAUUAAAUUUACUGAGGAAUCCAGAAUUAAAAAGCUCCACAAAUUGCUCAGUUACAAUCUGCCCUUGGAACUGGAAAACCUGAGAUCAUUGCUUGAAUCUACUCCAUCUCCAGUUGUAUUUUGUCAUAAUGACUGUCAAGAAGGUAAUAUCUUGUUGCUGGAAGGCCGAGAGAAUUCUGAAAAACAGAAACUGAUGCUCAUUGAUUUCGAAUACAGCAGUUACAAUUACAGGGGAUUCGACAUUGGAAAUCACUUCUGUGAGUGGAUGUAUGAUUAUAGCUAUGAAAAAUACCCUUUUUUCAGAGCAAACAUCCGGAAGUAUCCCACCAAGAAACAACAGCUCCAUUUUAUUUCCAGUUACUUGCCUGCAUUCCAAAAUGACUUUGAAAACCUCAGUACUGAAGAAAAAUCCAUUAUAAAAGAAGAAAUGUUGCUUGAAGUUAAUAGGUUUGCCCUUGCAUCUCAUUUCCUCUGGGGACUGUGGUCCAUUGUACAAGCCAAGAUUUCAUCUAUUGAAUUUGGGUACAUGUACCCGAAUGUGGUGACCUGGUGGCAUCAGGACAGUGUGGCUCAGCCCAGGAAGCCGGGGGAGAAGCCGCUGUCACUGAUGCUGUGGUUGCCUUUGGAGGUUGCCCUCACUUCCAGGCCAGCUGACCUUGCCUCCCCUGCUUCAGAGAAGUGCCUGCAAUCCUGAUGGGGAAUGUAGGCAUCUGCACCCUCGAAGUCCAGCUCUGACCUCAGUCCCUUCUGACACGGGACA